UGGGAUUACAGGUGUGAGCCACCGCGCCCGGCCACGUGCAUUUUAGAGCCAUCUCCUUUUCUUUCUUUUCUUAAACCAGUGUGAAAUGUACAAAACGUAUAACUAAUUAUUCUAAAAUGGACAGUCAGCAGUAUCUAGUACAUUCGGUAUUUUGCAGCCGCCUCUGUCUAGUUCUGGAGCAUCUUUGCUUGCCCUGAAGGAGACCCUGUACCCGUGAGCAGCCACGCCCAUCCCCUCUCUUCCAGCCCUAGGCAACCACAAGUCUGUCUUCUCUCUUUCUGCAUCUGCUCUUCUGGACAUUUCAUCUCAUGGAGUCAUGCAGCGUGUGGCUCUUAUGGCUAAAAUGUUCACUGAACAUAAUGUUUUCAGUGUUUAUCCAUGUUGUAGCUCGUGUCGGAGCUCUGUGCCUUUUUCUGGCUGAGUAAUAUUCCCCUGCGUGGAGGGGCCACACCUUUUCUAUCCACUCGUCCCUGACCGGAGGACGUGAGGCUUGUUUGCACCUGUGGGUGUUGUGAAUCGUGUUGCUCUGGGUACGUGUGUACAAGGAUCGAUUCCCGUGGAGAGCGCCCUGGGUCUGGGAUGGCUGGGUCACAAUAACGCUAUGUCUCACUUUUUGGGGAACCUCCAGACUGUUUACCACAGUGGCUAUACCAUUUCACAUCCCGGGGUGCCUGUGUUCGUUUGACUCAGAGCUGCUCAGAAACGAGGAGCGGCCUCACAGAGCGGCUGAAGGGGCGGCCCCUCCCGCACCAGGGUGAUUCCAGCCCCUGCCCCUCCUUCUGAAAGUUGAGCAGAGCGCCAGCCUCUCCCUCAGUGAGCCGCUUCUCCAUCCCGCGCCGCUGCGGGUCCACAGUGGGUGUCGGUGGCAGCAUUGGCUCCCAGGCCCACAGGAAGCCUCCCUGGUUCACAGGACACAGGUCCAUGACGUGGAUCCUAAGCCGAGUCAGAAGUGGAAUCCAAGCCAGGAUGGAGGUGGAAACCCUGAGGAGUCCGCCCUGUUGUUUUGGCUUUGUUGUGACAGGGGGUGGAUCUGCCUGCCGUUCGCAAGCAACGCGGGUGCAAAACAGCCAACCUGGGUGCAGACCUCAGGGGCCUGCGGACCACGGCUCCCCGGCCCUCAAACCAUGACCCCCGAAUCUAACAGGGUGCCCGUUUGCACACACGUGGGAGCGUACGGUGAGCAGGUCCUAGACUUCGGCUGGCCCACUGGUCUCAGGAGAAGGGCCCGACGCUCCUGCUGCGGUUGCAGUCGCCCCCGGCUCGGCGCGCGUCAGACCAGGUGCGCGUGGAAGUGUGUUUGUCUCCGCUAAUCCACGGGGGAAGGAGAAGGGCAGAGUCUUUGUCAGGCUCCGAGCAAUUAGGAUAAUUAAAAAAGAAGGCUUAUUGGGUAAACAUGCUCUGGGAUUGUGACCCCUUAAUUAAUGGACUACGGGGAGAAAUUACAGCAGUGGCAGGAUAAUUAACGUGUGCACUUCGCAAAGCCGGUAGACCAGGGUGUUGGAGGACGGGAUGGCCAGGCUGGUGCAGGGCGGCCGGGGAGGGCAGACGGGCCCUGCGAGGGGCGAGGCUCAUGGGCAACAGUGGGCAGCCUGGCAGGCCCUGGCAACUUGGGGCAGGUCACAGGAAGCCUUCACCCUCAUUCCUAUAGCUAGCUUAAAAAAAUCCAUCACUCUCAGCAGAAACCACAGCUGCCCCUGCAGCACCCCUUCCCCAGCUGUCUGCCUUAGCAGAGGCACAAGGGUGUGGGAACCCCAGAGUUCCCUGAAGAAGGGCUUCUUACCCCUAACCCCAGCCUCAGAGUCCAUUGGGGUCACUAGAGUAUUCUAAUAUUCCUGGUAUAUUCGAGGAGGGCAGCCGUGAGCCAUGACCCAGUCCAGGGGCUCCCAGCCUGCCCCACCGCAUGCCUCAGGGUGAGGGGCAGCGUGGGAGGCUUCCCCAUGCUGCGCCAAGCCAACUUCAGCUGCUGUAUUUUCAUUUCGCUUUACCUGAGGUGGCCCCAUGACCUGGGGGUCCUUCCAAAGGUUCCCACCCCCAGGGAGCCUGUCCAGGCCCCCAGAUCCUUGAUAGGCACUGCAGAGGCAGUGAGUCUUGGAGACAGGCGUCUCGGGCUUGUUUCUUGCUCCCAGGUGGGGAACAGAAGACAGGUGGGUGGGCUUUGGGAUGGGCUUUAGAAGGUGGCUCCAGGCCAGAGAGCAAUGGCCAUGGCCACUGGGCUUCUCAGGACCGAGGCUGGUUCAGUCCCAAGGAGCAGGCAGUGGCUGGGGUACCAGAUGGACAGCUGGGAGGAGGAGGACGGCCCCAGAGGAACACAAUCCCGGAGGAGGACAGUCGGGGAGAAGCGCAGCCCAGAGUAGGACAGUCAGGAGGACAGUCCCAGAGGAGGACAGUUGGGAGGAGCACAGUCAGGAGGAGCAGUCAGGAGGAGGACAGUCCCAGAGGAGGACAGUCCCGGAGGAGGACAGUCGGGAGGAGGACAGUCCCAGAGGAGCACAGUCCCAGAGAAUGACAGGGAGGAGGACAGUCCCAGAGGAGGAAAGUCCCAGAGGAGGACAGUCCAGGAGGAGGACAGUUGGGAGGAGGACAGUCGGGGAGGAGCACAGUCCUGGAAGACAGUCCCAGAGGAGGACAGUCCCGGAGGAGGACAGUCGGGAGGAGGACAGUCCCAGAGGAGCACAGUCCCAGAGGAGCACAGUCCCGGAGGAGGACAGUUGGGAGGAGGACAGUCCCAGAGUAGGACAGUUGGGAGAAGGACAGUCAGGAGGAGCACAGUCCCGGAGGAGGACAGUUGGGAGGACAGUCAGGAGGAGCAUAGUCCUGGAGGAGGACAGUCCCAGAGGAGGAAAGUCUCAGAGGAGGACAGUCCCAGAGAAUGACAGGGAGGAGGACAGUCCCAGAGGAUGAAAGUCCCAGAGGAGGAAAGUCCCAGAGGAGGAAAGUCCCAGAGGAGGAAAGUCCCAGAGGAGGACAGUCCAGGAGGAGGACAAUCGGGAGGAGGACAGUCAGGAGGAGGACAGUCAGAAGGAGGACAGUUCCAGAGGAGGACAGUCAGGGGAGCAUAGUCCCAGAGGAGGACAGUCAGGGAGGACUGUCCUGGAAGAGGUGAGUCCCGGAGGAUGACAGUCCCAGAGGACAGUCCCAGAGGAUGACAGUCAGGGAGGAUGACAGUCGGAGAGGAGGACAGUCGGGGAGGAGUACAGUCCCGGAGGAGGACAGUCGGGAGAAUAGUCCUGGAGGAGGACAGUCGGGGAAGACAGUCCCGGAGGAGGACAGUCCCAGAGGAGGACAGUCAGGAGGAGGACAGUCCAGGAGAAGGACAGGAGGAGCACAGUCCCGGAGGAGGACAGUGGGGAAGAGGACAGUCCCAGAGGAGCACAGUCCAAGAGGAUGACAGUCAGGGAAGAGGACAGUCCCGGAGGAGGACAGUCAGGAGGAGGACAGCCAGGAGGAGGACAGUCAGGAGGAGGACAGUCCCAGAGGAGGACAGUCCCAGAGGAGCACAGUCCAGAAGGAGGACAGUCGGCGAGGAGGACAGUCGGGGAGGACAGUUCCAGAGGAGGACAGUCCCGGGGGAGGACAAUCAGGCGGAAGACAGUCCUGGAGGAAGACAGUCAAGAGGAGCAUAGUCCUGGAGGAGGACAGUCGAGAGGAGGACAGUCGGGAGGAGGACAGUCCUGGAUGAGGACAGUUGGGUAGGACAGUCCCAGAGGAGAACAGUCAGGAGGAGGACAGUCCCAGAGGAGGACAGUCGGGGAGGACAGUCCCGGAGGAGGACAGUCGGGAGGAGGACAGUCCCAAAGGAUGACAGUCAGGAGGAGGACAGUCCUGGAGGAGGACAGUCCCAGAGGAGGAGAGUCGGGAGGAGGACAGUCCCAGGGGAGGAAAGUCGGGAGGAGUACAAUCCUGGAGGAGGACAGUGGGGAGGAGGACAGUCCAGGAGGAGGACCGUUGGGAGGAGGGCAGUACAGAGGAGGACAGUGGGGGAGGACGGCAGUUCCAGAGGGGCAGUUCCAGAGGAGCAGUCCCAGAGGAGGACAGUGUGGGCCCUGUUCGCUGAGUCUGCCAGGGCCUCCCAGAGGCAGACCUUGGUGUCUGCCACGCUCCUCCCAGUCCCGGCUGUGGCCGGCCUGCCUGCCCCGCCACGUGCAUGCAGGGGAUAUGCGGUGGGAGGAAAUGCUGGAGAUUUUCAAGGGCAGAGACUGGACAUUCACGCCAGUGUGGGGCCCCGGACGCCUCCAGGUCAGAAUGAAAGCCCCAGUCCUCUUAUACAGAUAUCCCUCGAGGAAGGAACGAAGCAUUUCCGCCAAUCAAGGAGGCUACUUCCCACAGCUAAACAGAGCCUGGCUCUGCAAGAUGUCUAAGAGCCCUGGAGGCAGAGUGAGGCUUCCUGAAAGACCCUUUUCUUCCUAGCAGAGCCUCCCUGGGUCUCCCACAGUGGGGAACAGUGACUAAGGGAAGUUUGGGGUGAAGAAUUCACUCUUAAGCCACUCCCAGCCAAAUCCAAAACAUAAAGAAAAUGGUAGCCCUUAGGAGCUCAACCCAGUGAGAACCCAAGGCCGUUGUCCUGCAGCGGACGUGGAAAUUCUGACCCUGUGAGCUGCCCUUGGGGGUGAACCCAUCUAGAACCUGUUCCAUGACCUGGAGCGUGAGGCCAGGCAGGGGGACUGUCUGGGUAGUCCAGGGGCCCUGGCAGAGAACCAAGGGCUUGCAUUUCUCAGCUUUGGCUCGGGGCAAGCCCAGGCUGCCUGGUGAUGUCAGCUGGAGGGGCACCUGGUGGCAGGAAAAGCUCCUGCCUCAGAGGCCAGAGAUGAUCCUGGCAUCACCUUGGCUGGCACGGGACCAUCUCUGACCCCCAGCACGGAAAGCAGCAGCAGGCCGCGGAGUCCUGGGCACAGGGCUCCCUUCUCUCUUCUGCUCCCAUCUGGGGAUGUCUCCCCACUACCACCUGCACACACCACCCUCACCGUCUGUCUUGCAGGUAGGAUAAGGUGCCUGAUCACAAGACCACACAUUGCCCUGGGACACACAGAAUGAGACAGCUUCUCCCAGCCAUGAAAGCACCUGUCAGCUGUCUACCAGGGGCUGCCUGGGUUGGGACACGGUGCCCACAUGGGUGUCAGGAGGACAAGAACUUCCGGUGCUUGCAGACGCUUCCAGAGGUGGCUGGUGGCCAGGCAGUGCUCAAACCCCAGGGAAUCUGGCUCACGGUUUCCUCCAGGGCGAAUUGGCAAGGCCCAGGGGCUCUCAGACCGGAUCCUGCUCAUCCUGCAUCUGCAGCACUCCACGGGGACAGGCGUGUGGUGAGAAGGUGGCAACAGAGUUGGCUGUAGUCGGGCGCUUUAAGGCCCAUCUAGAGAGGUAGGGGCUCUGUAGGGGGCUCUCCGUGGGGGCUCUUUAGGUUCCCAUGGUCUCUGAGGCCAAGGCUGGAUGUGUUUUUUGUUUGCAGCUCUCAGGGCACAGAGAAAUCCAUACCCCGGCCCACAGGCACGCGCUGGACUCUGUCCUGGGCACGGCGGCUAGAGUCGUGCAGCCUCUGCUGUGAGGCUCCUUCCGGGACCUCGGGGAGGCUCGCACUGGGGGCUCGGGAAACACCCGCCUCCUGGGGCUCCAUUCUCCAAAGGGACGUCCCGCCAGUGAGCCUGGGGACAUUCAUGCUCCACCCCAGCUCCCGUGUGCAGGUCCCCGGGUAACCUGUGUGUUGGCUGCAUCGCCUCAGUUCUGCAUUCGUUCAGGAAGAUUCGAAAGUUCCCUAUGAGAUGCCUGUGAGCCCCACCACCACUCGGAGCUCUGCCUGAAUGUGGGGUUGGGGGCCAGCCUUCCAGGCCUGGAACAAGGUGGGCGAGGCCGAGCCCAUCUCUGGAGCUGCCCUGUGCCCCCACAGGGAGGGCUGGCUCCCCUGCUGCCUGUGCCGAUGAAGGGGACACAGAGGCCUGGUGGCUUCACGGCUCUGCCACUCCCCAGCCUGGGCUCUGAGGGCCGGACCACUCUGAGUCUCGAGUCUUGUGUCUGCCACAUGGUGGGGACCUGGUCAUGGGACCGUCCUGGGGGGCUUACCUGAGGCUGCAGUUACACUAGUGCUGUGGUCGAGAGGGCAGCCGGAGUCUGCGUGGGAGAGGAUGUGCGUUCAGAACCAGAAGCUGGUGCAGAAAGCAGAGAGAGGAAGAAAGGCCCAGAAACAGGGAGGAUCCCAGGGGCAGUGGGGAGCAGGAGCAGGGAUGAGGUGGGCUCCAUGGCAGAGCAGGUUUUUACCCAGCUCUUAACCAUCCCCCAACGCUGGUUUCUUUGUUGGGUAUGGGGAGGCUGCCUCCCCAGGGCACCAACCUUGGAUCACCACCCCAGUGCCCAGAAGAAAGCCUGUUCUGCCAUUCGAGGUGCCUUCUGGGCAGGAGUGGGGAGCAGCAGUGACACUUCCACAUCUCUUAUGAUCCUACCCAUGGUGCCCUUGGCAUACUCUGAUCUGUGUGUGGAGGAGGUGCACAUAUGAGGGUGCGUGCACAUGUGUGUGUGUGGGUGGGUGGGUGUGAGUGAAUGUGUGUGCACAUGCAUAUAUGAGCUGCAUCUAUAAGGGUACAUGUCCAUGUGUGUACGUGGGUGGGUAUAUGGGGGCUGCAUAUAUAAGGGUACAUGCCCAUGUGUGCACAUGUGUGGGUAGGUGUGUGUGUAUGUACGGGCACGUAAGUGUGUGUGUGCAUGCAUGUGUGUGUAUGGCCUGCAUCUAUGAGGGUACAUUCCUGUGUGUGUGUGCAUGUGGCAGGUGUGUGUGCAUGGGUGAGCAUGUAAGCACAUGUGUGUGCAUGGAUAGGUGUGUGGGGGUUGCAUAUAUAAGGGUAUAUGCCUUUGUGUGCAUAGCGUGUGGCUAACUGCAUAGGCAUGUAAGUGUGUGUGUGUGUGUGUGUGUGUGUGUGUGUGUAUGGGCUGCUUAUAUGGGGGUGCCAGCCUACGUGUGGGUAGGUGCGUGUGCACGUGUGGCAUGUAAGUGUUGUGUGCGUGUGUCCCAGGCACCGUUCUCUCACCGUGGACUUGGUAUGGGGAGGUAAAAAAAAAAAAAAAAAAAAAAAGCCACUGAAAGGGAACCAGCCGCAUCCAUCUCUGAUGGGUGAAUUAGGAUCCAAAUUUUUAACUAAUUGAGUACAUUAAAUAGAAAGUCCCUAAGAAAGAAGGGAGGAAAAGACGAAUACAAGACACUUUUCAAAGCUUCUUUAAUAAAAAGUGUAUUUGGGAUUUGACCAUGAUGGCUAUCCUUGCUUGCCAAAACCUGACGCCCUGGCAGGUAACUUUCAUCAGGCAUCUCUGAAAUGGUACCUAAAUGAAUUAGCAAUAAAAUGGACUUAGGCCGAGCAGUGGGGGCCUCCAUUAAUCUUGGGUUAAUCACUAAAGAGGUGCCAUUCACUUUUCUUAAGAAGUCACAUUUCUCUCCCCUUGCUGGCGACCAGAUUUCAUAAAGUAACAUAUUUCUAAUGAAAGGUCUCUGCUUGAAUUAAACCCUGAAGGUUUAUGCAGAUUUUGCGUUUGAUUACUGCUGGCAUGGGCUCUUAGCCGGCUGCGGAAGGAAGGUCCGUUCUGAAAGGGCCCCAGCGUGCAGUUCAUAAUAUUCUUUGAAAUAAAAUAGUGCACUUGUGCUUAGUGGCUUUAAUCAGCCCUGACUUUUGAUAGUCAAACAAUAGCUAAUUACAGUAGCACCUGCCUUCCAGGCUCUGUCACGUCGGCUCCUGCCGGAGCGAGGCCUUGUCUGCGAGCUGCGUGAUUAUUACAGACUCUGUCUGCACAAAGUCGCUGGAGCUGACACCCAGCAAGUUUGGUAGCCAUUAGGGAAGGUUUAUUUUGCUGCUGCAUGGCUGGCUUUUCCAUUACCUUCUUCUCCUUUGUAUGUUUGGGGGCAGUGGUGUCGAGGGCAUGGAGGCAUGAGGAGGCAUGUUAGGGUGUGGGUCCCGGGUCCUGAGACAGCCGGCUUUGGACACAUGGCACCUGCUCAAGGCGUUCUUGCUCUGGGGAUGCAGGAUGCACAGAUAUGCUGGGAACUUGCUCGAGAUUUGAGAAGGGUGUUGUGAAUGCUUGCCAUGUACCGACAGCAAGGUUGGACUCUGAGCAUCCCCCAGCCCAGCAGGAGCACGGAUCUGGCUGGCUCCCAGGUGCGCCUGGCAGAGCCAUUCUGGACGCUUAGGUGAAAUGUGCCGCCAGGCACUGGGAGCAGGAGGCGGGCCCAGUGGAAGUCAUAAAUUACUAUCUCAUCAUAUAAGUCUUUCCUUUCUCAUUAAUUUUGCCUGGUAAAUGAACCUGAGUUUGCCAGAAUCCAGCCAAGUGAGUAACAUCGGCCUGUCAGCCAUGGGCUUGACAGACCUUGUACGUAACAAGUUCCCGGAAAGGAUCAACCGGAUAUCGGGAAUGAAAAAGUGGGGGCACCCCGUCCCAUAGACACAGGCCAACCCAGCCUUCGCUCCUUCCUGCCUGCCUGUCUCUCCCUGGCCCCUCUGCCCACCCCUACCCCGCUGCAGGACACCCCCAAGAUGAAAGGGCAAGGAGAAGGAGGGCCUGGGGGACCUGGCUACCAGGACUUCCGGACAAACAGUUGUCAGGCACUCGGCAUGCCCCGAGGUGGGGGGGUUCAGGACGGGUCACCCUGUCCUGGUGCAGGCAGCACUCCUCGGUGGGGGCAGUUUUGGGCACAGUGCUCGAACCAAACGCCAGAGCCGGUCCUGCCCAGUGCUCCAGUUCCCUCAAGAACUCCAUCCGGUCCCCUCCAGGAGAGACCGGGCAGGGCUCAAAGGGACCUUCCUCCUGGACUUUAGGUGACCUUUUGCUGAGGGUGACGUGAGAACCACCAGUGAGAGCCAGGGGGGCGGGAGGGGAGUCAUUCCAAACUGGGGAGAGCCGUGCACAUCCAGCGUGGAAGUGGGUGGCACCCAGCCAGGCCCUAGUCUCUUCUCGUGGGGCCAGCGUCUGAAGAUGCCCUCCCAAGCCAUUCACAUUGCGGCCAAGACCAUGUUUCCCUUUCUCUGUGACCCAGCUGCGCCCUGUGGGUCUGUGCACUCCAGCACACGCGUGCCUGCUGCGGCCUCCCCGGUCUCUCUCACGCCGUGGGUGCCAUUUCCGCUCUGCCGGCUUUGGUCUCCGGACACCACGUCGUGUUGACAAUUACCCACAGCCAGGACUUGCCAAAACCUGGAGUUGAAAGGGCUUCAAGGGGGGAGAAACCAACUGGAAAGCUGUUUUCUGUUAAGGCAGGUUUAUUUUUCCUUGCAAUUAUGUCUGACUAAAAUGUCCUUGUGCGGGAGUCACUUCCCAAGAGAGGUCUGAUUCAUCCUGCCCUGGGCAGCCCCCCGGCCCCCGCCAUCCUCGCCAGGCCUGCCAUUGGGCCCGCGGUGGGAGUCCUGGUCUCAGCACCGCAGACUCCAGCAGCGACCAGGCCUCUUGAGGGGCUCUGUGGGUCCAUCCCAGGAUGGAAAGCACCCCUGAACCUCUGGGAGCUCAGGAGGGGAGCGUGGACUCUGCUCGUGCCCGGCCCUGAGCUGCCUCUGCUGUGGGAGCCUCUCAUACCUACAUGAAGUCAGCUGCAUGAAGACUGGCCAGCGACCCGGACCCGCCCGCAGGAAGGCCCCACGGCCCUAACUCCGCCGGUGUCUGACCCCGAGCUGUCCCAGCCCAUGGCCUAGAGGAAGCCCAGGGUUCACAUCCCAGGGAAGCUGCAGGGCCUUGGCAGCAUGUUCAGCUCGUCGGCCCCAGCCAGCUCGAGGUGCCGUGAACAGAGCCAGCGAGGGGUGCCGUGAACAGAGCCAGCGAGGGGUGCCUGUUUCCUCACGGUUUCCCCUUUCUCCCUGGAGAACAGCGCCAGCCGCCUUGUAAAUCACCCCUUUGCCCCGUCUGACAUCUCCUGUUGCCUGGGCCGCCUCGGCCUGGACCCUGAGGCCAACCUAGUGAUGGAAAGAGAGCGAGCCCUAAAGGGGGCUGGGCUUGGUCAAGUUCAGCACUUCCUCCGCCAUCUUCUCCCCAUCCCCCAUCACGACCCCGGGCAGCGUCUGCCUCUCGUCCCCGUGGUGUUUGCCAUCACCAAUCCGUUUGAUUGAUCAUCUCGGUGGCCACAGGUUGGUAAUAAAGCUGGUUUCAGAGCCUCUUGCAUUUCCCCCAGGACCCCGUUGGCAUGACAGGACUUGACACCAGCCAUUCGUCACCUGCUGCCUGUGGUCUCUGCACAAUGACCAGCAGACAGACAAGAGCCAGGCCAGGAGGAGGCUUCGGGAGAGGCUGGGCCUGUGCUCAGGGCUGAGUGAGACUAGUGGACGUGGCCGGCCCCAUGCCUCUCUGUGCACGGCUGGAUCUUGCAAACAGUCGAGUCCUGGCUGCUGCGCCACCCGGGGAUGGCAUCGUCUGUCACACGCUUCACUCUCCCUGUGGCGCACUGGCAUCCACCAUGCCCACCUCAGAGGCCAGGAGGCACGUCAGCCGGGAAGGCUGCAGGGAACCCCCAAGCCCAGGCCACCAGGGCCCUACCCUGCCAUGGGGCGCACUUGCUCAGGCCUCUCCUCACCACAGGGUCUCUGGGUGCCUCUGUGAAGACAGGAUCCCAGUACAGGAAAGCCCCAGGCUGGCCCCGACCCUCUCCUUUUCUGGGAGGAAAAAUGGGUUUAUGUUGUGAAUCCGCUGAAGCCCCUGGGACGUUGUCCAGGGACAGGGUCAGUGAAAAUGUCUCAAAGGUCGGGGACUGGGCACAACGAGGCAUUGACCCCAGAUGAAUCCACAGAGCUCCCGGAGCAGGGGAAGUAGCCCUUGUUCACCCACAUGCACACACACACGCGCGCACACACGCACACGCACACACAUGCACACACGCGCACACACACGCACACAUAUGCACACACAAACGCACAGUUGUGAACACGAGCAUAUGCACAUGCACACACGUGCACAGGCACAUGUGCAUAACCACUGUGUAAACACACCCAGGCACAAACAGGAACACAGACCCAUACACUCAUGCACAUGAGCACACGCACUUUUCCAACACCGUGAAGUCCGUGCAUCCGGGAGCUCUAGGUCAGCGAUCAUUGCUAGCAGGCCAUGGGACCCUCUCAUCUGAAAAGGAGGGAGGGCAGGGCAGGGGCUUGUAACCAAGAACUGUGUCUGGGGUCAUUCCUAAUUCAAGUCUGAGACAGUGUGAAGGCUUCUUCUCAUUCUCAUGGCCAUUUCCCCAACCCCACCCAGGUCCCUAAAGCCCUAUCAUAGCCUGGCCUUACCGUCCUCGCCUGGUUUUCCAGCCUCCCACCCUGCCUGGGGCAGAGAAGACCCCCUCAAGGCCAUGCUGCAUCUCCUCCAGCAUCCCAAAUCCUCCCCAUGGGCCAUCUCCCACAUGGUGUGGAUAAAGGGGCGUCUUUCCUAGGGACAGCCUGGCUGCGCCCUUGCAGCCACACCUAGGCCUAAUACUGUCUGGAUGGCAAACAGGGAGCUGAAUGAACCCCACUGCACAGGCAGGACCCCAGGGGCAGCCUGCAGAGUGUGGGAGGGGCCUGUGUGGAGUUCACAUUCAUGCAGGAUAUUUCAGCAGCAGCACAUUUGCUCACAUCGGCAACCCCCUCUUCUAAGCACCCACCUAAAGCGCAGUCACUAGCAAAUGGAACAUCCCUGUGCUGGGCAUGAAACAGGCCCUGGAACCUCAGCCGCACCCGGCACCCUGCUGCCCGGCGGGGCCUGCAGUCAGCCAGGACACCCGGCAGCCACAAGGCCGCCCUCUCUGGAGCCUGUGGUCUGGUUCGGCUAGGGUAUUGUGAUCUGAGGACCCUUAGAAAACUGGCCACCCGAGAACUUUUCCAGUGUGACUGCUGGCCUCUCUGGCAGACGUGUCCAAACUCAGAAAACCUCUGCUGCUCUGACCACAGGGAACGUCAGAGGGGACGGGGCAGCGGAACAAAGCACAAAGCGUCCCUGCGUCCUCUCAACGUGGCCCAGCUCCUGCAGACACUCAGCGAGCCGUGGCCUCUCCCAUCCUCCCACGCUUCCCUCCGGCCGGCCCUGGAGAUCCGUGGAGCCACACGGUGCCGAGCGCGGCGCUGGCCGUGUGCUCCGUGUCUGUCAUCGUCAGCCCUGUCCACCUUUGGGGCAGGGGCAGCUGGGCUGGCUCCAGUUUCUCUCCAUGUCAACUUUGCAAAGGAAGGAGGUGGAUGCAGAAGCUGCCACCAAUAGCCACGUGGGCAGCUGUGGCCCCGAGUCCGGGGAUGCAGUUGGUCAUCAGGAGCCUCGAAGCGUCGCUCACCAUGCCUGGAAAGACCGGCGGCCUCUCCUGCCCAGGCGCAGGCCCUCGGCUCAGCAGAAGCCCUGCAGAAGCUGGAGCAGGAGGCAUCCCUGGGUCCGGCACAGCCUGUGGUCAGGCCGCCUCUGCAGCGGGGCAGGGUAGAUGUUCUCCCCUCAGAUCUGAAACGCAGAGAGGAAGGGCGGGCCCUCGCGGUGCCUCGGGGCAGCUGUGCUGAGCAGUGUCAGCCGCUCCGGGCGAGGGACCAAGUGGCCACACUGGCCGCAGAGCUGCCCUGCCCGGCGGCGUCAGUCUGGGACGCCCUGCACGCCUGCCCCUGCCACCAGGCUGGCUUCCUUCUGAGCUGCCUCGGCCGGAGACCCCUUGUGACUGGGCUCUCUGUGGAUGACAAAAGGAAAGACUUGAGCAAGAGGCUCUGAGGAAGGUGCCGGCCCCUCUCCAGACUCCUGUGCCACAGGCUGAGGACGGGCAGCCGUCAGGGAGAGUCUGUGCUGCAGGAGGGCAGAGGGUCGGGGGAGUGGAGCUGAAGGGGAUGGUGGAGGAAGGAAGGCAGGACAAAGGGGCCUCCACCGCCUCCUGCCCCUUUCCCCAUUGCCUGAGGACCAGAGCCUGCGGGGGGGUGGGGACAGGGAAGUGGCCUCCUGGGCCAGCAUAUCCCUGAGCCAGUGUGGAGUGGACAGGCGGCCCCUCCUCCCACCCCCCCCGGGCACCCACCACCAAUGUGGGUCCACACCAUUCCCCAUGACGUCAGCCGAGAAGCAUGAGCUCGGUCAAGACAAAACCUCAUGGAAUCCCGAGUCUUUUAAAAGAAAUAUUGAUUUAUUUUCCAAUCACGAUAAUGCCAUACUUUUUUUGUAAAACAAGCAGGGUGAAAAAAAAAAAACAUUUAAAUAAGAAAGUCAGAAUUAUCCAUGAGUCCUCUAUUGCUGUGUGGAAGCCAGUUAUGGUCAGAGAGAGACAUUCAGCACCCACUGCAUGGGUAGGGGGUGGCUGCCCCGAGCUGGUCACCAGCUUAGUGCCAAGUCUGUGGCUUGUUGAAGCCGACUCUGUGUGUUCGUGUGUUGGUGUGUGCAUGUGACGUGUGCACAUGAAUGUGCGCAUGACCUGGUGUGUGUGCACGUGUGUGUGCAUGCUUGCAGCCCAGUGGCUGUCUCAGGGGACAUGUCUUCAAGUGUGUGGCUCCCUGUCUCACCUGGGGCAGGUAUAUCUGGGAGGGUGCAGAGUUCUCUGUUUGCACACAGAGGAAGUGGUUUUCUGCCUGAGUCCCCCCACCCUUACUGCCAGCGUCCAACCUCACACCAGAGAAAAGCCAGAGUUUCAUGUGCGGAGGGACGGCGUACAUUCCAACAAGGUCCGUCCUUCCCACCUCAGGCCUUCCAUCGCCUCCCUCGACUCCCACCUGGAGCCUGGAGGCAGCUGGAAGAACCCACCUCUCACCCCAGCAAGGUCUGUGGCGUUAAGGUCACACUGGCACCAACUAAGAACUAAGACCUUCUCUGAGGCAUGAAGGCUGUUGCUUAGCUUUGAAAACAGUAAAUGUGAAUGAAAGGGAACCUUGAGAAAGACCCGUUCCUAGGUGAAGUGAGAAGCAGGCUAGACUGGCCGUCCCGGGCCAUACCCACCCUGUCUCCAAGGGGUCUCUGCCCAGGAGAAAUCAAAGUGGGGUUCUCACAGCCCCUGGGGCAGGGGCAGGGAAAUUUGGUCAGAAACAAUGCGGAGCCCCCAGGGCUUUUGUCAAAUCUCCAUCCAUGGGUUUUGUUUUCUCCCCAGUUCUGAAUCUGGGAGGCCGAGUGGCUGCCCAGCGAGGUUGGCUCUGGGCUGAGGACAGCACUGCCUGGGCCUCCUUCCCUGGGUGGUUGUUCAACACCGGGCAAGUCCCUGCACCUGUCCAGCCUCAGCCCACUGUCUCAAAAGUGGGGCCAUUGGCAUUCUGGACUGUCAAGAAGCUUGAGAAACUGGGCCCUAGGAGGAUGCUGCAAGAUGCCCAGAUGUCCUCUUCAACUCGAAACGUUGCCAUCUGCCUUGCUGGCUCACACCCAGCCCCUACCUGAGAACGCAGCUGUGGGCACUGUCGCCCAGGAGGAGGCCUGGCUGCUGAGACGCUCCCUUCCUACAGCUGCCGGUGGCCAGAACCCUCCACCUGUGCUCCAGACCAGGCUGGCACUGAGACGCCCACCCCAGCCAUGGUCAUUUAGAAAUAAGUAGGUGUCCACUAUAUGAAAUCGAAAUAGGGAUCAUUCCUGUGCCUGCCAAUAAAACACCAAUCUCCUUGAGAGAAGCAGCCUUGAAACUUAUCAGUCAUUCACAACUUAGCAUGAUCAGAUUGAUGAGCUAUGAUCAGAUUGAUUGAUUAGCUAUGAUCGGUUUGAUGUGCUCUGAUUGGGUUCACUGAUGAGCUAUGGUUAGAUUCAUUGAUGAGUUAUGACCAGAUUGAUUGAUGAGCUAUGAUCAGACUGAUGUUCUGUGAUCAGGUUCAUUGAUGAGCUAUGGUUGGAUUCAUUGACGAGCUAUGACCAGAUUGAUUGACUAGCUAUGAUCGGUUUGAUGUGCUCUGAUUGGGUUCAUUGAUGAGCUAUGGUUGGAUUCACAGAUUAGCUAUGGCCGGAUUGAUUGAUGAGCUAUGGUCCGAUCGAUGAGUUGCUUUCAGGAAACCAGGGAUAAGGAGCAGGCAGACGCCAUCCCUGUACCAGGGGGUGCAGGGUGCUCAGGGAGACUGGAGCCCCAGUCUGCCUGGAGCUGGCAUGAGGCCAAGGUGGGCGCCCGCAGCCCUGGAUGUGGAGGGGUGUUCUAGAAGGAGUGCUGGCCUGCAGGAAAGGCCUUGGGCUGCAGUCAGGUCAGCCAUGAACCCUUCAGUCAAACAUGUGACCUGAACUGAGAACCCCAGGUCCAGCCUCUAGGUAUGGGACGCCAGCUCUCUCCUUACCACCGAAGCAGCUUUGGGCUUGCACAUGAAAAGCUUCCGAACCUUGACUCCCUUCACAGGCCUGAGCAGUGAGUUCCCAGAAUGUUCUAGAAGAGGCAUGUGCUCAGGGAGGCCAUGCUUCAGUGUGCAGACGUUUCCCCAGAGAGGUCAGCAGGUGCCGGGCACCAGCCCUUCCCCAGACACAGGCUGGCCCUGCCAGCUGGCUUAGCAGGGCGCUGCCUGUGUGUGGAGUGGGGGCUCUGGGCUCCUUGCUUGGCCCCCACAGGUCCUCGACCCAGAGACCUUGUCCCCCCACUGUCGGGCUUAGGACAGGCCAGGGUCACCCUCAGCAGAACCUGGGGCCAGCGCCGCAGGGCCCCCUGGUUUGGAAAGCCUGUUCCUCAGCUCUGUCCCAGCGGGCACUUAGCUGAGGAUACCCCUGAUGCUGCUCCAUGCACACCUCUCACCACGAUUCAAUCCACCUGAGGAUGGUCACCUUCUCAGGGAAAUGGGGAAAGACUUAUUGCCAAGGUCACUGAAGCCUUCCUGGUCUUGGUGUCUGGAAAAAACUCGCCAAGAGAGCAGGCAUCUCCCGAGACCCAGGAAUCAGCAUGGCCACCAGAGCUGGUCACUGCCACUCCGAAGCUCCUCAGGCAGCUUCCUUUCUCCCUAGGGAGGAGACACUGUUGUCCGUCUGAAGCCUGGCGAACGUGGGACACAGGAGGCAGCCGUGGCCGGAGGGGCACGAGGGUGGUGGGCAGCCAGCGCUAGCCCAAGCUCCCGGGGUCACUCCAAGGAGUAGUGAGGGCUCCCCUGCAGGUGCAGUGAGAGGCGUGGUAGUAUUAGGGCGGUUAGAGGAGGGGCGUCUCCCUUCCCUUCCUUCUGAGUUUUCUUUGACACUGUCAUCUUUCAGUGCAGAGUCAAUGCUGCAGAAGGCUCCCUGUGAGACAGGCGAGGCUGUGAGGCCGGGUGGGAGGCAGCGCUUCCCGAGCAGGUGCGGGGUGCGUCUUCACUCUGCCCCUCCCGACACUUGGUUUUGGAGGGGUCUGACCCAGUGGCCGGGCUCAUGGGUGGGAACUGGCCAGCCAGCCCCUCGUCACCUUCCCUCCUGCUUGGGCUCCACAGCAUAUCCCAGGCACAGCUGCCCAUUAGAGGCGGGGCUGUCCCUGCAAUGGAGGUGCCAGGGAAUGUCUGUCCAGGCCUUGGCCAGGGCCCGGGGUGGCUGCAAAUGGCCUUAGGCCAAUGAAGGACACAGCUGCCCCCCAACCUUGUUCAUUCUCCAAUGCCCCUCCCUCUGUCCCUCUCUCCCUCCCUCCCUCCUGCAGCCAGACCCUGGAGGUGGGCUCCAUGGCAUAGGACAGCCCCAGGCAGACCCAACUCACCCACUCCCCAGAGUGGAAAGAACAGCCUCUGCCCCACACUGCGCGGUGCCCCUAGGUCCACAGCAGAGACAGACACACAGAAGAGAGGGGACGGACAGCGAAGGGUUACGGGGACCAGACCUCAAGGUCAGAGGAAGAGAGAGGGGACGGUCAGCAAAGGGUUACGGGGACCAGACCUCAAGGUCAGAGGAAGAGACAGGGGGUGGUCAGCGAAGGGUUAUGGGGACCAGACCUCAAGGUCAGAGGAAGAGAGACGGGGCGGUCAGCGAAGGGUUAUGGGGACCAGACCUCAAGGUCAAAGGAAGAGUAUAUUUCCCGCCUGCUUCCCCCAGCAUCUUCCAGCAAAGCCGGCUGGUGGUGUUGCGGCCACACAGCCUCCCCGACCAACAUCCAAGCCUGCAAAGCUAAGAGGUUAGGAUCUGCAGGAGCCCAGGUGCCUCCGCGGGAGGAAUGUGGCUCAGAUUCGGGGGACCGGUGCGCGGUGUGUCCAGGAGACGCAGGCACAUCGCAGGGUUGGAAGUGCGCUGGGGGCCUGGCCUGUGGUCCUGGCUGGGAUGCCGCCAUCCUAGGGUAGCGGGCCUGGGGGGGCCUGGAGCUGGGGGCCAUCCUCCCAUGGCCUGGGCCUGGGGCAGGGGCUGCUGCCCGCCACCCGCCACCCGUAGCCCGCCCGGGAAGCUGGGGUGGAGGCGCCCUCUAUCGCCUGCCUGGGGGACAUCUCGCCAAAGCACACCGGUUUGCAAAGGCAAACCGACAUUAAGCGUCCCAGGUUCCCCAGACAUUAUCUGCCUUUUGGGAACCUUUAAAAUAAAGAGUCAAACGUUUUCGGCCCCUGUCUGGCUUUUUAUGUAAACUGAGUGGUUCCUGGAGUGUGUUUUUUAAAGUGUUAAGAUGGCAGUAUUUAUCUGGAGGGGGAGGGAGGAAGAGCCAGGUGGGCGUUCUCCUAUUAGGCCAGAAUUUUCAGAGAAAACCAGUGUAAGGCGUGGCCAAAAUGAUGAGUUUGUUUCCCGGUGGCCUAGGAGUCUGUCCAGAGCAAAGCAACUGCCAGGUGGGCUUCUCCUGGCACUGUCGCCGUGAAGCCUUCGGGAGCCAGGACCUGCCAGCAGCCAGAGUUCAGCCCUGCAGGGAAAGGGGCGGCCAGGGGGAGCCCCACACCCUGAGAACGUGGGAGUGCGGUCUUGAUACAGAUCAUCUUCAGAUAGACUCUGUGGCCUUAUGAUGGGGAAUCUGAGGGUUCAUUCUCAGCCAGAGAGGAGGAUAAGGGGUGUUGCUUCUAGAAACGGCCAUGCGUCUUGGGGGCUUCACGGAGCACCUGUGAGCCUGGGGUGGCCAAGCCUGGGAAACCCAGCGUGGUCCCGCCCAGGCCAGGGCAGAGCAGAGAAGGGUCAGAGCUGGAGGCCGGGCUGAGGAGUCUGCAGCCGCCAGGGCAGCUUCCGAGCUUGGUGCACCUACUCACCACGCUGGCCCUUCCUGGGCUGUAAGCCCUGAGUGACCUGCUCCCCUCUGGGCCCGGGCUUUCGGAGGCGAAUGUUGGUAGGUUUCUCUGGCCGGUAUAGCCCUUGAGCAUGGAACGCUUCACCUGGUGCCCUGGACGGGGUGCAAGGGAGGCAGGCUGGCACUCUCUGGCCCCCCCAAGUUCUGGGCCAGCCCCCAGCAUUUCCUGCUGAGAGUCCCAAGGUCCUUGGUGAGGUUUUCAGAGCCCACUGGGCAAACCUAGGGUGAGGUGGGCUGUGUGGACUGCAGCCAGGAGCAAAGUCUGGCCUGGGGCACCCCAGCCCUCUGGCCCCAGCCCCGUGGAGGCCCCUGCCUCUCCCCUCCAGCUGGCCACCUGGGCGUUCUGAUUACCUCUCCAGGUGUGGCUGGGAAAGCAGCUCUGCCCUCUGCCCUCACCCCAUUGUUCCCCAGGCUCUGCCUUUCAGGUCGUUUUACGUUUUCACCUGAUCCCUGUGAUGCUGCAAAGCAUUCCCAGGCCACUGAGCAGCCCUGCCACAGCCGCUGUGUCGCCCCCACUCACAAAUCUCGGGACGGACAUGUCCCCUGCCUUCCUGGGAGCAGGCAUGCUCCCAGGAAGCUGUGACAUGCUCGCUCGGGAGCUUGGAGCUGUGACAUGCUCGCUCGGGCUUCUUCGCUCACACCCGCGACAUCCACAUUGGCCGUGGUCAUAGCCAGCCUGAGCCCAGGGCGUGCUUGAGCCCCUCCGUCUCUGGUCCCUGGACGGCCAAGGUCAGUUUCCUCCCCCUGGAAAUGGCUAGAUGAAGGUCUGCUUCUCCAGAUGCCAGCCUUGCUCCCAGGCCAUGGCAGAGGAAAGCCCCCCCACCACCGGACACCUGGCAUGUCCACCUGGGGAAAGGGCACUGGCCCUCUCUGGCAAGAGCUUCUCAGACCCCAGGGUAGGUGGACUUUGUGGUUUUCAUCUCUGCCGAGCGUGGAGCCCAAUCAAAGAUCCAGGCUCCGCUGACGAGAAAACCCAGAAAGCCCCUGCGGCGUGACACAAGGAAAAAUAAAUAUCAAAAGAACAUUUGACGAGCUCAAUAAAUUGAUCAUAUUGUGCUGAACCUUCACCCCCAUAACUAUGGGACCAUUUAAAUGCUAAUGCCAUUUUUUAAAAAGUCAAUUACAGGAGUUUGCAAGGAAUGGAGUCAGCAUUCCCCACGACAGCCUCUCCUCCUCCAGCUCCCUCUCCUCAUCCACAGGCACUGGGGCCUUUGCUCCCCUGAAGGAAAUGUUCCCUCACAGUGGUCCCAGUAAUUGAAUCAAGUUGAUACAGACACCAGGAAUAUUGCAAGUUGUGUGGGUAAUGGGAAGCACGUGUUGAUAAAGUGGUCAGUGUUUGCGGACCAAGGGGGGCCGCAACUGCAGUUAACCCUUCAGAGAGCACAGCGUCCCCACAGCCCGAAGGGCCGCCCCCUGCCUGGCAGAGCCCCAGGUGGGUGACAUGCAAGCAUUCCGGAAUCUUCCAGCCCUGGGUUCCUGUUUCCCAUCAGCACCUGCUCUGCUCUGCAGACGGCAACAUGGCCACAAUUCUCCCUCCUCUUGGUGGCACCUCCUCACCAACUGGACCCAACCGAGCCUGCAGCCUCCUGAAUUGACAUGCAGGAGAGGAGAAAGAAGAAGACAUGGACCCCCAGAGAAAGCUGGAUGCUCAGGAACCCCGUGUCCUCCAUAAGGGCCUGAGGGCCUGGGGGUUCAGCCUUCUGCACCCCCAAGUUCCUCCCACACCAACUGUGCUGGUGGCAAAAUUCUAGUCACCAUUUUCAUACCGACAGCCUCUACGUGCUGGGCGCUUAACUCACAGGAGACCUGCAAGCCUCACUCGGGGAAACAGAGGCACACAGAGUGGAGGGGCCGCCCAGCUCAGAUGCAAGAGGAUGGAAAGCAUGGGACUCAAAGCUGGGUCUGCCCACCCUUCCUGGGUGCUGGGACUCAAAGCUGGGUCUGCCCACCCUUCCUGGGUGCUGGGACUCAAAGCUGGGUCUGCCCACCCUUCCUGGGUGCUGGGACUCAAAGCUGGGUCUGCCCAACCUUCCUGGGUGCUGAGUCUGCCCACCCUUCCUGGGUGCUGGGGCCCUGUUCCCCUGACCCUCAUUUUCCCACCCUUGAUCUGGCCCAUGAGGUCCUGGGGGCCUGGAGUCUUCCUGGGGUCAGCAGGAGGCCUGCCCCACUGGGGCGGCAGCAUGGACGCUGGGAAGUGGGACCUGGACGCUUGAUGUUGAAACCGUGGUGCCUCCAGGAUGCCCUGAGCGCCGUAGGAGAGCUCCACUUCCCAGCCACGCGGGCAUCCAGGAUUGCAUUUACCGGGGCUGGAGGCGCCCCGCCACGCGGGCAUCCAGGAUUGCAUUUACCGGGGCUGGAGCCGCCCCGCCACGCGGGCAUCCAGGAUUGCAUUUACCGGGGCUGGAGCCGCCCCGCCACGCGGGCAUCCAGGAUUGCAUUUACCGGGGCUGGAGCCGCCCCGCCACGCGGGCAUCCAGGAUUGCAUUUACCGGGGCUGGAGCCGCCCCUGCCACGCGGGCAUCCAGGAUUGCAUUUACCGGGGCUGGAGCCGCCCCGCCACGCGGGCAUCCAGGAUUGCAUUUACCGGGGCUGGAGCCGCCCCCUGCCACGCGGGCAUCCAGGAUUGCAUUUACCGGGGCUGGAGCUGCCCCUGCCAUGCGGGCAUCGAGGAUUGCAUUUACCGGGGCUGGAGCCGCCCCCUGCCACGUGGGCAUCCAGGAUUGCAUUUACCGGGGCUGGAACCGCCCCGCCACGCGGACAUCCAGGAUUGCAUUUACCGGGGCUGGAGCUGCCCCUGCCAUGCGGGCAUCGAGGAUUGCAUUUACCGGGGCUGGAGCCGCCCCCUGCCACGUGGGCAUCCAGGAUUGCAUUUACCGGGACUGCAGCCGCCCCGCCACGCGGGCAUCCAGGAUUGCAUUUACCGGGGCUGGAGCCGCCCCCUGCAUGGAGCCUCGCACACCCUCAGGUUUCUCACCCCGGCUGGGGCAGCUGCAUGGCCGCAUUUCACAGGGAGAGUGUAAACUGCUGAGUUACAGGCAGAGCCCUGGGCUCAGGGGUGGGCGGAGGCCCUGACCAAGCCCAGGGCCAUGGGGGCUACAAGGAGGCAAGGCCCCUAAAGUCAGGCAGGGCCAGCUAGCUGCCCGGCCAUAGGAGUCUGUCCACACAGCGCAUGACAAACAGAGUGCCCAAGGAGCCAGCUGGUCUUAGCCUGGCAGAGGUGCCAGAUAAUCCAGCACUGGAGGCUGUGGCUGUGGAAGGCUGGCCUCUGACCCUCAUGCCCCCAGGCCCAGCACUUGGGACAAGCAGCUGAGACCUAGGGGCCUGCGGUGAGGAGGUCCCUGGGUGUCCUGUGUGGACCCAGGCUCAGGGGCAAGGCCAGGCAGCUGGGACCCUUCCCACUCCCCGCUCUGUCUCUCUCCACCUCAGUUUCCAGACAAAGGCCUUCUCUGGGCUCUAUGUCCCACGGCUGGAAGGGAACGCCCUCACCUUGAGGGCUCCAGCCUGCUUUUUCUGAAUCCCAGGGUCCUGGCUGGGAACGCUCAGAUGUUGAGACCUGAGCCUGUGGCCAGGAGUGGUGGCAAAAGGGUCCUGUGGGCCCCCAGCCCAGCUCCAGCCCAAGCGGGGGACCAAUGCCUGUGCUCACCUAGGGGUCCUGGUGGGACCGAGGCCACCACCACCCAUAGCCCCUCCCCCACCACCCCAGGGGCUCUAAAGAUGCAAACCUCCAAGGUGUAGAUAAGAGAGACCCAAGUCCUGCAGCCAGGAGGGGCAGCCUCUCCCUGCAGGAGCCAAAGAAGGGCAGAGGGGCAGCCAGCCCUCCCUGCCUUGCAGCAGGGAGCAGACAUCCCUGGAAGGGGCAGGGGCCAAAUGUCAUGUGCAGGGUCCAGGCUGCCCCUUCUGGGGGAGGAAGUAGGGCCUCCUGGGUGUUCUCCUCCCACAUUGACCAGUGCCUGCUGCCCCUGGGUCUUUGAAGCUUCAGAAGUUCCCUAGAGUGGAAGAGCAGACCAGGGGCCUGCCAUCCUUGCGUGCUCACCACCUCCUCACAGGGCCUAGGGGCAGGGGAACUUGGCUGGCUGCCCAUGAGCCCCUGGCCGAAGACCCCAAGCCCUGCAGAGGAGGAGGCUGAUGCUGCAUCUGGGGUCCCACUGCCUUUUCCCUCCUGUGCUUGUCGCCCGGCCCCUGCUACAGGGCUCAGGUGGGAACACCUCUGCGUGGAGGGAGACCCACCAGUGUGGCCACGGGCAAGGCCCCUGAUAAGGUCACAGGUGGGGAGGACCAGGGCUGCUGAGACUGAGGCCCAAGCCCCCUGCCUAGGCCCCCAGAGAUUCCUGGGUGCGCUGGCAGGGAGGGGGUCAGCUUGGAAAUCUGCAGGUGGGCAAGCUCUCUGGUGUCCCGAUGCCCGCCGGAGUCUGAACGCAGCCCCUGCAGGUGCCAGAUGGGUGUCUGUCGACAAAUUCACAAGUACCUGCCUGCAGCGAGUUCCCACCUGCAGCUUCCCCACGCUGUUUUUGUUUGGUGCUUCCAGAAAUCAUUUCAUCCUCCUCACCCACACUGGUGCCCACCCUGUGCCAGGGCUGGGGGCUUGGGUGAAGGAAGCCCAGUCCCAGUGCCCACAGCCCAGCAGGAGGAGACAGACACAUUAGCAAGGCCUGCGGGCAGGUCAGGAGCUGGGCGGGUCCACGGUGAGCCCCAGAGCUGCUGGCAGAAGCGAGGAUGGCCUUCCAGGGGAGGGAACGGCACAGGCAAAGGCCCUGGGGCAGGACAGCACGGAUGUGUCCAUGGAACAUGGGACAGCCACGGCCUUCACAGCUGCUAUGCCUGUGGUGUCGGCUCUAGUUCCAGGGCAAAGGAUGGAAAGAAGGCCGGGGCCCCGCUCCCACCCAGGAGUCAGGACCCCACUCCCUCCAGGGCACCGAGACCCCACUCCUGCCCGGUCACCAGACCCCACUCCCUCCAGGGUGCCAGGAUCUCACUCAAUCCAAGUCACCAGACCUCAAUCCCUCCAGGGCACCGAGACCCCACUCCCACCCCAGGCGCCAGGACCCCACUCCUGCCUGGGGCUGCCCCUGCUGCUGUGCCUCCCCUGGUGGAGCGGUUUCUGGCUUUAAAAGUGUGCUCGUGAGCGCAGGGUGUUUUUCCUGAAUGAAAACUCACAGAGUGCAUGUGUCAUGCUGAUGUGACAAACCCGGGCGCUGUUCUCCUGGGUAUCACACCCUACGACUCCAAGGCUGGCCCGGCACAGGGGCUCCCCUUGAGGUGGGCAGGUUUCCAGGCAUUUGGAAGUAGACAUGGGAAGGAAGGAGCGACGGGGUGGGAGGGAUCUGCCUGCCAGCCCACAGGGCUCAGGGGUCCUCAGAGGUGUCGCCCCUUCCAUGCUCAAAAUGGCUGGAAGAGGAGAGCCUCUCAGUAUCCCCACCUUAUAGAUGAGGAGGCACAGAGAGGGGGAAAUUUGCCGGUUCCCCAAAGAGCCUGCUGCCUCCACCUGCUGUGUUCGAAGCGGUGAUUUUUCUCUUGAGGCCCCUGUGUCCUAGCAUUUCUGAGCUCAAAGGAACCUGUGUCUGGCCAGCCCCUCCCAUGCUGAGGACAGAGGUGAAUGCUUGGGACAGCGAGAGGUGGCAUCACUGAAGAAGCCCCGUGGCUCCGGCUCCGUCUGCAGGAUCCCUCCCAGGACGCAGUGGUGGGCCCAGGCCGGCCAGCGCUGGCUGAAGGAGCACUGUCCCCACAACCCAGGGAAACAACAGGGCUCCAGGGGGACGUGCAGGGAGUGGAAGAAACUCAAGCCGGGAGCUGUGGAUCCAAAAAUAUUGCAGAGUUUCCCGAGGCAGGCCCUACGAGAUCCCUGAAACGGGAUACGCCGAGCUGAACUUGGCCACAUAAUGCCGCUCUGUUUGGGAAGGGCCCGGAGCACUGGGGGCCCGAGGUAUCUUUCAAAGAGUGAUGGUUACGGAAAUUAGUGGUGCAGAAAUCCAUACUCAUCAUUCAUCGGGGGCCUUAUUAACCUUCUUACGAUGUGAUAGGAGCGGCUUGGCCUCCUGACUCCAGGGGCCUGGGAGAGGCCAUCCUUGUCUCCGGCUUGGAGGAGAGAUGCAGGAGGAUCGCCCAGGCAGCACCGGCCCCACCCGCUUCCGGAAUCCUUGGAGACACGAGUAGCAGUUUCCUGAUGUGAUACUUAGGUCAUGAGGCAGGGCGUGGACCAGGACGAUGCACAGCUGAGAGCAGCCCACACGGCCUCUCUCGGGGUGGCAAUAACACUGCCUCAGAGACUGGAGAGAGCCAGGCCCAGGAGACCCCAGUCAGGGCGUUCCCAGGAACAGGGAACCCAGAGAGGCCUGGGCAUCACACACACCUGCGCUCACAGUGGCCCCACCUGGACCCCUGGGGGACCCACCCUUCUUCCCCUUCUGCCCCUGUGUUGCUUCCUCUGCACCGCAGGGGCCAGGUAGCUGCCAUGGAGUUGUCUGCAGGUUAAGGGAGGCCAAGGAAAGGCAUCUGACCUUUGGAAGAUACCCCAAUAAACACCAUCCGCUGUCAUCACUGAUCCAGCAGCUGAAACAUGGAAGGGCCAGCUCCAGGGGCCCACAGGCCUCGCAGAACUCAGAGCUCCACACUCCUCCCGCCCCUGCCCAUCCCCUCUUGAAGGGGCCUCACCAGGCCAUGGGCUCCCUAUUAAGUAAUCACAUCAAUGUCCAUUUUAAAUAAGGUCUGAAUGCUAUGAAGCACCCGUGUUGGGUCAAGGCAGCUCUUGGCAGUGCGGGGGAGCUUGUUAGAAAUGCAAGUCCCCUGAACCCCAGCACUGGGGGAGACGGGGGUUCUGUGUAAAUGCCCGGCAAGAGAGCUGCAUUCCAGUUUGAGACCCACUGGGUUGGACAUAGCAGGUGAACGCUGGUCCCAACAGCUUCUCUCCUCGAAGGGAACAGUGCACCUCCCACUGCUCGAGACCAACCUGGGAGGCUCCCAGGGCCCCUCCUGGGCCUGUCUCCCCCCACACAGCAGGUGCCUUCUCCCGGGCUCCUUUGGGGCCUACCCGGUGCCUGGCACCCUCAAGAUGCCUUUACAUCUUGUGUUUUGGGCUUGGCCGCAGGACCCCGCAGGAAGGUGCAUGGCCGCUUCAGCAAGGCUGGCGGAGAGGGCAGAUUUUCUGGGCCCACAGGCCUUGGCAGGAUGCUGGCCUCUCAAGGUUGCACUGACAACCUUGGGCACGUGACGGAUUUAUUGAGGGGAGAGCAGGUUGAGCUGUUCUGUCCAAUGCCGUCGCCAGGAGGAACCUGCCGUGGCCCGGCCUCAAGUCCUGUUACUCAACACUUGUCUUAUUAUGCUGCAAAGCCAGAGCAGAGCCGAGGUGAUAACGCGGGCACGGCAGGCCCGGGCUUUCCAAACCUGCUCAUUUUUAGCCCCUGGGAAUCAAAGUGGUGUCCGGCUCUGUCCCGCAGCCUUUGAUCCUCCGCCCAGUGUCUCCAGCGAGAGAGAAGCAAAGAACACAGAGAGAUAAACCACACUUGAGCCGUCGCUCUCCGCCUGGCUGCGCCUCUAUCUGGGGCCGCAGCGUCCCCCGAGUGCUGAAAAGAGUUCUCCUGGUGAGCGGCACCGUGACCUUCAUUCUUGACCGCGCUGUCCGGAUGAGAGUGGCUUGUCCAGACGAGAGUGGCUUGUCCAGACGGAAGGGGAAAGGACGGUCUGCCUGCUCUCCUGAAGGGAAGGGCCAGAUAGCGAGGGAACCCACCUCCCUUCCUGUGGGGUGGAGGUUUGGGGGUGGAGGUGGCCCCAGGAGACAGGGGUCACGGAAUUGGCGCGAAGGGAAGAAUGGGGAGCCCAGGCUGAAUGUUCUCCACCAGCACAUCGGUGGGGGCUCAGGAGGCCAGUCCCAUUGCCAAGCGAUGAAACUCUUGUAUCUUCGAAUGGCCUGGGUGGGUUUCCGGCAGCCAAGAAGCGUGAGCAGCCCUGUGGAAGGAGGGGAAGAGGCACUGGUCUUUUCCUGUUUGUCUUCUGUGGGUUGACCCUCACGGAGGCACUCCGCUCCGGGCAUGACCUCGGACUCUUGAGGAGCCUCAGUUCGGCUGUCUUUCUGCAGUUAAUUACUAGGACAAGGGAACACAUCCAGGUGCCUUUCACAGGGACAUCGCCCAUGAGGGCAGGGACUGCACCCUAUUGACCCUAUAUUCCACCCCAGCUCCUGGCACUUGGCCGGGGCUCAGACACGUGUUGAGUGAAAAACUGCACAUUUGGGCAGAGUUACCAGCAAUGAACCUGCCUCUGUAGAGGAUCCUAAGUCGGGGCGAGGGGGCCCUCAGUGAAGCCUACAGAAAGCCAAGCAGCCCAGGGGUUCCCUCUCCACCUGAGAAGCAGCGAGACCCUGUCCAGGUCAGCGGGACCAGCACCGCAUCCCAGGCCACCCGUGUGUCAGCACAUAACCUUUGAAAACACCGUGAAUGCCGGCUUUGAUGAUAAUAUGUGGGUAAAGGUUGUAUUGCUAUCUGGGUGAUGAUUCAUCCGUCUGUGAACCGGGACAAGGAGGUAAUAGGAAGGCGCGAUGGCCAGGGGCAACGUUGGAACGCAAACUUAUCAGAGGCAGUGAACUCCGCGCUGCACUAAAUAGAAUUCCAUUAUUGUUUCAUAAAUAGAGAGAUUGAAGUACCCAGGCCAGGAACCGAUGAUCAGAGGGGAAUGCGUUUGAGCUCCGCUCUGAAUAGUAUUUGUUCUGAGUAAGUGGUUGUCUCGGCUAAUAGUAGGGUAUUUCAUUGUUAAGAGCUUGUUGAGCAGGAUUUAUGGGUGAGUCCAGCACGGCUGUUUGUGCAGGAUGCUCAGUGGUCGCCAGGGGUCCGGGAGUCGGCAGCAAUGUUGUUCCAUCCUUUGUCGGCUUCUCCAUCUCCUGGUGAACGUUGCCCCUUGGAGAGGCGAUGGCGUGGCCCGGCCCCGGCAGGUGUCUGAGGGCCUGAAGGCACCCCCGUAAUCCCAGCACACUCGUGGGUGCCGGCAGUGUGUGAGUGCGUGCGUGUUGUGUGUGCAUCUGUGAACAUAUGACAGGAUUCGGGUUUCUGGCUUCUCUAGAAGCCUGGGCUAGGCCAUUCCCCUGCCUCACUGUGGCGGCUCCUUACUCCCCCGGGGGCCAGGCGUUCCUGCCAUGUGCCCACCUGAGCCUUGGCAGUCAGAAAUGAUGGUACCUACCUAGAACCUGCCUACCAGGUAAACAGGCGAAACCUAGAACCUGCCUACCAGGUAAACAGGCAAAAUCUUGUCAGGUAUAAAGAGCUUCUCUUGGGGGCAGAGUCUGCUGGCUAGGAAUUGCUGUGGAGUGGGGGUGUAUCCAGGCUGGAGGGCACCCCCGGACUUCUCCCCAGGGAGAAAACAGAUUGAGCCCUUCUCUCCAUCUUCUCACCAGCUGUGGUUUCAGAGGCACUUCCAGCAGUCCUGACCCCACCUCAGGGUUUUCUCUUCCAAAGGGGCUACAGGAUUGAGGUAGGGAGGGGCCCCAAGAGCCUCUGACUUCCCCCCAGAUCACCAGGUAAACCCAUGGGUCAGUGUCCAGCCCCUCUGCCCCAACAUCAGCAACACAGCCCUCCAUUCCAGGGCCCCUGUGUGUCCCCUUCCUCCUCCCCCCAGGAACAUCCCCGGAGCAGCCCGCGUUAGAACAGGAUCCCGACGGAUCCCGUGCUGCCUCCCCUUCAGCCAGCGCCAUCCUCUGUCCCCCAGGCCUCGCGGGCUGGGCUGCGUUUGGUUGAGCAUUGACAAAGUCACCUCCAUUCUCCUCCAAGAAAAGCCCACGAGAGACUCAGAGGCAAGUGCUCAUAAAGAAUCAAACACAAACCAAGCCCAGGUCCUGAUCACGGGCACGGCCAAUGUUUUUGUUCUUAUUUUCCCUUUUCUCUGAUCACACGUACAAACCAGAACCAACCCCACGUGCCUUAAGAAACACAGACCCAGGGGAGAGGGGUAGACCCCACGGAAGUGGCCAUCGGUGUCAGGCCCCGUCUCAGGGACAUCUUCCCCCGCCUGGUCACUGCAGGCAGGCUAUGGCAGGUUCUGGGGUGGUUCACCCCUGCACCCUCAGCCCCACUGGGCUUUCUUCGAGGUGCUCUCCUGCCUGUGGGCCCAAACUGUUAUUUAAAAGCCACCUCUGCCUCCCAGGGCACCCAGGUUGUGGCCAGCCCGUCUGUACAUUCUUGGCACUGCUGAGGUGAGAUGCAUGAGGUCCCUGCUCACAGAACGAGGAGCCAGGCCAUUACAGCUACAGGGUAUCCAGGAAAGGCAUCAGGUGGCGGGCAGGACAGCUGGCUUGCAGGGUGAGCCCCUCCUGGCCUCACUUUCCCCUCUUUAAAUGAGGGUGCAGCUCAUCUGAGAAUAGGUAGGAAGGUGCCAGUGCUGGGAGGGGACUGGGUGGCUCUCUGGGCUCCUCACCGCGGCUGGUCCCUCGGGACUUCCAUGAUGGGCUCACGGAGGUGCGACUUCCUCCCAGAUCCCUCGAGGACCCCCUACAGCCCAAACCUCCAGGAGCACCAGCGUGUGGGGGCUGGGAAGAGAGUGUCCUUCAAUGCAGGUGUGCAGGUAGCCAUGCACAUGUGCGGGGUGAACAAAAGGCCCCUUCACUGUCACCUCCCCGGGGGCCGUAACUCAGGAGCCGAGCGUCCUCCUCUCCCUCCCACCGGUAGCAGCAGACUUGACCGCCAGGCUCUGAGGCCUGCACACCACGCUCGCCCACAGUGGGCUUUGUUUAGUCUGGGGGAAGCUCCGUUGACAGGGUUUCUGGGCGAUGGGCUCUUUUUUCUUCCGAAUUCUUCCAGAAUUCUGUAGGCUGAAGACACCACGCGUGCAGCCUGAGGGGAGAGUAAAUAACCCUGUGAAGUGGGGAAGUUCCUGCCUCUCCGGAGGGCUGCCAUGGGUCAAGCUGUGCAUGGUGAGAACUGGGGUAACUGGGGCGUGACACCUCUGCCCCCACAAGAAGCCCACUGAGACAGGACCUGCCCUCCCCAAUCAGAAGAGCUUGUGCAGUGGAAUGUUCCAGAAGGCCUGGGUGGGGCUGGGCAGGAGGAAGAGCCUCAGCAACCGCACUCCCAUCCUAAGCUGGGGACUUGCCCGAAAGGACAGCUGGAGCCAUUUUCAAGCCUCAGCCUGGGCGGUCAUCUGCUCAGAUCCACUCCGAGGGUCUCACUUCCUUACGUUCCGGAACCGUACGGGUCAUGGUGGAGCGUCCUGGGGAAGUGGCUGUCGGCUUGGUUAAUGGGUCCCUGCUGGCUGUGAGGCACACGACCAGUGCCCUCUGGAGCUGCCGUCCAGCCCCAGUUCCCAUCUGCAGGGACCCAGAGUCACAUUCGCCUCCUAGAGAGGUGCUCAGAGUCGUUAUGGUCCGAGAGGCAGCCAGGGAGCUGCAGAAAUGGACAUAAACCCGUCCAUUCUCCUGCAAACACUUCUCCUUCCUCCACUCUGUGCGGAACUGGGGCCGGGGGCAGAGGUAGGAAUGGGCACAGCCUGGCCUUCCGGAGCCUGUCACUCAGUGGAGGAGGCGAGAGGCUCCACCAGCCCUAACCCGGGGCCUCGUGUUGCUGUUUGAUGUGCAGGAGAGGAGAGAGGCCAAGAGGGAGCCAGGAGUGGCUUCCAACAGGGGGACCUGGCCCAAAGCCAGGGGAGGCCGUGGGUGCCUGUGAGGGCAGGGUGGGCACAUGCCAGAGGUUGCCAUGGGGGUCGUGUGUGGACCAGGAUGGGCAGCCUGGAUGCAGAGAGGGGCUGAGUAGGAAAGGAUAUGGCCGGGAAGGAGGGCUGAUUUGUUUUCAGAAGAAUCUUUUCGUGGAACUCUCGUGUGCCAUUGUUAAGUGCAGAUGUUCCUGGACUUGGAAUGGGGACAAGUCCCGAUAAACCCACUGCGAGUUGAAAAUAUCCUAAGUCAAAAACGCAGUUCACACACCAAACCCACCGAGCAGCACGGCUUAGCCUCACCCACCUUAACGCGCUCAGACACUCAUAUCAGCCUACAGCUGGGCAAACUCAUCUAACACAAAGCCUAUUUCAGGGUAAAGUGUUGGCUGUCCCACAUAAUUUAUUGAAUACUGUACUGAAAGUAAAAACCAUAAUGGCUGCGUGGGCCCUCAGUGUGCGGUUUCCACUGAAUGCGCGCAGAUCUCAGACCUCGUGGGGUGUAGGAGCCCUAAGGGGAGCGGUCAGCCCUUGUCCUCUGUCCGCUUUCUGCCCAGUGGCCCCUCCAGGUCCCGGCGUCUCCUUGGACUCACAUUACCAGCAUUUCUGUCCAUUUCGGGUGAGACCCGAAGCAGCGAGACCCUAUCCAGGUCAACGUCUGGUGAG